AGUCCAGCCGUCCGCUGCCGCGUUCGCAGCAUGGCCGCCCUGGGGCGGCCGGGCUCGGGGCCGCGCGCUGCGGUGCCCGCUUGGAAGCGUGAGAUCCUGGAGCGGAAGCGGGCCAAGCUAGCCGCGCUGGGCGGGGGCGCGGGGCCCGGGGCGGCGGAGCCCGAGCAGCGGGUGCUGGCCGAGAGCCUGGGCCCGCUGCGCGAGAACCCGUUCAUGCUGCUGGAGGCCGAGCGGCGGCGCGGCGGGGGCGCGGCGGGGGCGCGGCUGCUGGAGCGGUACCGCCGCGUGCCUGGCGUGCGCGCCCUCCGCGCCGACAGCGUCCUCAUCAUCGAGACGGUGCCCGGCUUCCCGCCCGCGCCGCCCGCCCCGGGGGCCGCGCAGAUCCGCGCCGCCGAGGUGCUGGUGUACGGGGCGCCGCCCGGCCGCGUCAGCCGCCUACUGGAGAGGUUCGACCCGCCCGCCGCGCCGCGCCGCCGCGGGAGCCCCGAGCGCGCCCGCCCCCCGCCGCCGCCGCCGCCGCCCGCGCCGCCCCGGCCCCCGCCCGCGGCCCCCAGCCCGCCCGCCGCGCCCGGGCCCCGCGGUGGCGGGGCGAGCCCCGGGGCCCGGCGCAGCGACUUCCUCCAGAAGACCGGCAGCAACUCCUUCACCGUCCACCCCCGGGGUCUGCACCGCGGCGCGGGCGCCCGCCUGCUCUCCAACGGGCACUCGGCCCCUGAGCCCCGGGCCGGCCCUGCCAACCGCCUCGCGGGCUCCCCGCCUGGGUCGGGACAGUGGAAGCCAAAGGUGGAGUCGGGGGAUCCCUCCCUCCACCCGCCCCCCAGCCCCGGGACCCCGAGUGCCACUCCAGCCUCACCCCCUGCCAGUGCCACUCCUAGCCAGCGCCAGUGCGUCUCCGCAGCCACCAGCACCAACGACUCCUUCGAGAUACGGCCGGCCCCCAAGCCAGUUAUGGAGACCAUCCCCUUGGGGGACCUCCAGGCCCGGGCGCUGGCCAGCCUCCGCGCAAACUCUCGAAAUUCUUUCAUGGUCAUCCCCAAGAGCAAGGCCUCCGGGGCUCCUCCUCCUGAGGGGAGGCAGUCCGUGGAGCUGCCAAAGGGAGACCUGGGCCCGGCCUCCCCGAGCCAGGAGCUCGGAUCCCAGCCGGUGCCUGGAGGGGAUGGUGCGCCUGCCCUCGGGAAGAGCCCCCUGGAGGUCGAGGCACAGUGGGCAGUCGAGGAGGGGGCCUGUCCCAGGACAGCCACCGCCCUCGCUGACCGGGCUAUUAGGUGGCAGAGGCCGUCCUCACCGCCCCCCUUCCUGCCGGCUGCUUCGGAAGAAGCUGAGCCUGCUGAGGGCCUCAGGGUUCCUGGCUUGGCCAAGAAUAGCCGGGAAUAUGUGAGGCCGGGGCUGCCUGUCACCUUCAUCGAUGAGGUAGACUCGGAGGAGGCCCCCCAAGCAGCCAAACUACCCUACCUCCCGCACCCUGCCAGGCCUCUGCACCCUGCCAGGCCCGGGUGCGUGGCAGAGCUUCAGCCCCGGGGCAGCAACACCUUCACAGUGGUGCCCAAGAGGAAGCCAGGGACUCUGCAGGACCAGCACUUCAGUCAGGCCAACAGGGAGCCUCGGCCACGGGAGGCCGAGGAGGAGGAGGCUAGUUGCCUCCUGGGGCCCACGUUGAAGAAGCGCUACCCCACCGUGCAUGAGAUCGAGGUGAUUGGCGGCUACCUGGCCCUGCAGAAGUCCUGCCUCACCAAGGCUGGCUCCUCAAGAAAGAAGAUGAAGAUCUCCUUCAACGACAAAAGCCUGCAGACCACAUUUGAGUACCCUUCCGAGAGCUCCCUAGAGCAGGAGGAAGAGGUGGACCAGCAGGAGGAGGAGGAGGAGGAGGAGGAGGAAGAGGAAGAGGAGGAAGAGGGAUCCGGCUCAGAGGAGAAGCCCUUUGCACUCUUCCUGCCCCGGGCCACGUUUGUGAGCAGCGUGAGACCCGAGAGCUCUCGGCUGCCAGAGGGUAGCUCAGGCCUGUCCAGCUACACCCCGAAGCACUCUGUGGCCUUCAGCAAGUGGCAGGAGCAGGCGCUGGAGCAGGCCCCGAGGGAGGCAGAGCCCCCGCCCGUGGAGGCCAUGCUCACACCCGCCAGUCAGAAUGACCUCUCGGACUUCCGCAGCGAGCCAGCCCUGUAUUUCUGAGCCCAGCACUGCCAGGACCAAGGCUGAGCCCAGCUGUGGGAGUCCCGGAAGCUGGGCAGUAGCCAGGGACUACUGCACCCGCUUCUGCCUUGUUUGGCCUCACUGUAUCCCACCCACCCCUCCUGGCCCUGGAAGCAGCUAGGGUGCCUCCUGCCAUCGGGGCCAGGUCUGGGUCUCACUCCCCGGCCCUGAUUUGGGAGGGUCCAAGGGGGAAGUGGGGUGGGGAACUGCCUGUGGGUGAGUGCCAGGGGCCUGCUGGGUGGUGGCCAUCUGCGACCCGGCAGGGGGCUGUGCAGAUUCUGCACCUGGCCAUUCCCUGUCCUGUCUCCUCAGCCUGCCUCACAGUGGCCAUGGGGUGUCGGGGUGAAGGGCUGUCCCAGCUACUUGUCCUCUGCAGGACCCUAAGCCCCUGCCCGCAGCCCACAUGCCCUCUGUGAUGAGUGGCGUCUUUCCUGCCUCUGAUGAUGGACUCAAUAAACAGCACUGGACAAGG